AGUGAGUUUCUCAUCUAGGAAACCAUCAGCAGGCCAGGCUGGACUGCCCCAUUUCUAGCCCCCUUUCUUCUCUGCAGACUGCCCUGUUUCUAGCCCCUUUUCUUCUCUACCCUUUUCUGUAGAGUGCGUUAGACCCAUUUUACAGAAGGGGACUCUGAGACCCUUUCUUCUCUGCGGGGCAGGGUAUGUGGUUCAGACGAGCCGCUUCCAUCCCCAGUUCUGUCCCUAAGCCCUGGGUGACCUCAGCAUUGAGCAUCGUCUCUGAGCCUCAGUUUCCUGUCUAUAUCUAGUGCCACCAGGCAUCAGAAACGGAGUCUCUUGCUCUGGUUCUUGCUGUUCCUGCUCCUGCUCCCGCCGCUCCCCGUCCUGCUCGCGGACCCAGGGGCGCCCACGCCAGGGGCCUCUUUGGGAGGAAGCCGCAGGCACCAAGGGAAAUGAGUUCCCUUUCUCCAGCCUCUAACCGUCUGGGAACCCAUCCUGAUUCCCAUUGCCAGUGGAGAAGGUCUCCCCUGGUGAAGACUUCGGGAGAACAUGGGAGAUGGAAAUACAUUUAGGAGCCGGGAUGCUUCAUCUGGGGUUUAAGAGAUCCCCAUUGAGCAAAUGAGGAAACCGAGGCUCAUGAAUCCCUGUUGUUACUAUCCAUGCCAGCACCAGGGCAUCUGUGUCCGCUUCGGCCUUGACCGCUACCAGUGUGACUGCACCCGCACGGGCUAUUCCGGCCCCAACUGCACCAUCCCUGGCCUGUGGACCUGGCUCCGGAAUUCACUGCGGCCCAGCCCCUCUUUCACCCACUUCCUGCUCACUCACGGGCGCUGGUUCUGGGAGUUUGUCAAUGCCACCUUCAUCCGAGAGAUGCUCAUGCGCCUGGUACUCACAGUGCGCUCCAACCUUAUCCCCAGUCCCCCCACCUACAACUCAGCACAUGACUACAUCAGCUGGGAGUCUUUCUCCAACGUGAGCUAUUACACUCGUAUUCUGCCCUCUGUGCCUAAAGAUUGCCCCACACCCAUGGGAACCAAAGGGAAGAAGCAGUUGCCAGAUGCCCAGCUCCUGGCCCGCCGCUUCCUGCUCAGGAGGAAGUUCAUACCUGACCCCCAAGGCACCAACCUCAUGUUUGCCUUCUUUGCACAACACUUCACCCACCAGUUCUUCAAAACUUCUGGCAAGAUGGGUCCUGGCUUCACCAAGGCCUUGGGCCAUGGGGUAGACCUCGGCCACAUUUAUGGAGACAAUCUGGAGCGUCAGUAUCAACUGCGGCUCUUUAAGGAUGGGAAACUCAAGUACCAGGUGCUGGAUGGAGAAAUGUACCCGCCCUCGGUAGAAGAGGCGCCUGUGUUGAUGCACUACCCCCGAGGCAUCCCGCCCCAGAGCCAGAUGGCUGUGGGCCAGGAGGUGUUUGGGCUGCUUCCUGGGCUCAUGCUGUAUGCCACGCUCUGGCUACGUGAGCACAACCGUGUGUGUGACCUGCUGAAGGCUGAGCACCCCACCUGGGGCGAUGAGCAGCUUUUCCAGACGACCCGCCUCAUCCUCAUAGGGGAGACCAUCAAGAUUGUCAUCGAGGAGUACGUGCAGCAGCUGAGUGGCUAUUUCCUGCAGCUGAAAUUUGACCCAGAGCUGCUGUUCGGUGUCCAGUUCCAAUACCGCAACCGCAUUGCCAUGGAGUUCAACCAUCUCUACCACUGGCACCCCCUCAUGCCUGACUCCUUCAAGAUCGGUGGGGGCAGGAACAUGGACCACCACAUCCUGCAUGUGGCUGUGGAUGUCAUCAGGGAGUCUCGGGAGAUGCGGCUGCAGCCCUUCAAUGAGUACCGCAAGAGGUUUGGCAUGAAACCCUACACCUCCUUCCAGGAGCUCGUAGGAGAGAAGGAGAUGGCAGCAGAGUUGGAGGAAUUGUAUGGAGACAUUGAUGCGUUGGAGUUCUACCCUGGACUGCUUCUUGAAAAGUGCCAUCCAAACUCUAUCUUUGGGGAGAGUAUGAUAGAGAUUGGGGCUCCCUUUUCCCUCAAGGGUCUCCUAGGGAAUCCCAUCUGUUCUCCGGAGUACUGGAAGCCGAGCACAUUUGGCGGCGAGGUGGGCUUUAACAUUGUCAAGACGGCCACACUGAAGAAGCUGGUCUGCCUCAACACCAAGACCUGUCCCUACGUUUCCUUCCGUGUGCCGGAUGCCAGUCAGGAUGAUGGGCCUGCUGUGGAGCGACCAUCCACAGAGCUCUGAGGGGCAGGAAAGCAGCAUUCUGGAGGGGAGAGCUUUGUGCUUGUCAUUCCAGAGUGCUGAGGCCAGGGCUGAUGGUCUUAAAUGCUCAUUUUCUGGUUUGGCAUGGUGAGUGUUGGGGUUGACAUUUAGAACUUUAAGUCUCACCCAUUAUCUGGAAUAUUGUGAUUCUGUUUAUUCUUCCAGAAUGCUGAACUCCUUGUUAGCCCUUCAGAUUGUUAGGAGUGGUUCUCAUUUGGUCUGCCAGAAUACUGGGUUCUUAGUUGACAACCUAGAAUGUCAGAUUUCUGGUUGAUUUGUAACACAGUCAUUCUAGGAUGUGGAGCUACUGAUGAAAUCUGCUAGAAAGUUAGGGGGUUCUUAUUUUGCAUUCCAGAAUCUUGACUUUCUGAUUGGUGAUUCAAAGUGUUGUGUUCCUGGCUGAUGAUCCAGAACAGUGGCUCGUAUCCCAAAUCUGUCAGCAUCUGGCUGUCUAGAAUGUGGAUUUGAUUCAUUUUCCUGUUCAGUGAGAUAUCAUAGAGACGGAGAUCCUAAGGUCCAACAAGAAUGCAUUCCCUGAAUCUGUGCCUGCACUGAGAGGGCAAGGAAGUGGGGUGUUCUUCUUGGGACCCCCACUAAGACCCUGGUCUGAGGAUGUAGAGAGAACAGGUGGGCUGUAUUCACGCCAUUGGUUGGAAGCUACCAGAGCUCUAUCCCCAUCCAGGUCUUGACUCAUGGCAGCUGUUUCUCAUGAAGCUAAUAAAAUUCGCUUUCUAAAGUUACCUGUUAUAUAUCUCUUUUGGUCCCAUCCUCUAAAGCAGAGGCAACACUGGAACAUGGCUAGCCUUUCUUGUAGCCAUGGCUGGGCGUGCUAGAGGUUGCAGCAUGAGACUUUCUGCUGGGAUCCUUGGGCCCAUCACUGUAUAGACAUGCUACCACUGGUACUUCCUUUCUCCCUGCGGGCCAGGCACUGCCCUUUUCAGGAAGCUCUCUUAAAAUACCCAUUGCCCCAGACCUGGAAGAUAUAACAUUCAGUUCCCACCAUCUGAUUAAAACAACUUCCUCCCUUACAGAGCAUACAACAGAGGGGGCACCCGGGGAGGAGAGCACAUACUGUGUUCCAAUUUCACGCUUUUAAUUCUCAUUUGUUCUCACACCAACAGUGUGAAGUGCGUGGUAUAAUCUCCAUUUCAAAACCAAGGAAGCAGCCUCAGAGUGGUCGAGUGACACACCUCACGCAGGCUGAGUCCAGAGCUUGUGCUCCUCUUGAUUCCUGGUUUGACUCAGUUCCAGGCCUGAUCUUGCCUGUCUGGCUCAGGGUCAAAGACAGAAUGGUGGAGUGUAGCCUCCACCUGAUAUUCAGGCUACUCAUUCAGUCCCAAAUAUGUAUUUUCCUAAGUGUUUACUAUGUGCCAGUUCCUGUAACAGGUGUGGGGACACAGCAGUGAGUAAUCAAUACAGACAAGGUUCUGCCCUUAUGGAGCUCACACUCCAGUGGCAGACAAACAGACCAUAAAUAAGGAAACGAUGAAAUAAGAUAUAUACAAGGUGAGUGUGACUUCCCUUCUAACCCCCUCUGCUCUGUCCUCCCCUAUUGCGCUCUCAAGACCAGAGACCCAACAGCAGUGAUCUCAGGGCAGACAGCCCUCCACUCCAGCUCUGAGACCCUUUUCUCAGGACCUCUGUAGGCAGCAGAGAGAGAGGACAGAGGGGUAAGAUGAGGGGUUGAGGGAAGGUUCUUCAUGAUCCACACUUUGGGCUUAGUAUUUCUCAGGAAGAGCUAUGGCCCAGAAACAACAGGGGAAACUAGAGUUCGGUCUGACAGUCCUUGGGGUUAAGUCUCCUGUCUUAUGGUCCAGAAACUCCUGUUUCUCCUUAGUUGGCUGGAAACUGCUCCCAUCAUUCCUUCUGGCCUCUGCUGAAUGCAGGGAAUGCAAUCCUUCCCUGCUCUUGCAGUUGCUCUGACGUAGAAAGAUCCUUCGGGUGCUGGAAGUCUCCAUGAAGAGCUUGUGUCCUGUCCUUUCUUGCAGAUUCUAUUUCCCCUCUUCUGCUAAUACCUCUUACUUUGCUUGAGAAUCCUCUCCUUUCUUAUUAAUUUCAGUCUUGGUGGUUCUAUCAGGGGUGCAUUCUGGCCAAGGGGUGGGCCUGUGAAUCAAUCCUGGGCAAUCAGACACCCUCUCCUUAAAAACUGGCCCGUGGAGACUGAGAUCACUGACUCUGACUCAUCCCCACAGCUGGCUCUGACAAGAUGGUCCAUUUGUUCCUGCUUCCGAGAUCCCCAGGGCAGCCUGGAUCCCUGCCCUUCUCAAGACUUUAGCUUUUCCUUCCAUCCGGUGGCCUAUUCCAGGAAUUCCUCUUUUGCUUAAAUCAGUUGGAGUUUGUGUCUGUUGCUUGUAAUCAAGCCUUUAUGGCUGCUGGGCUGAGUGACACAAGCACUUUAAUGGCCUGGAGGGACUUUUAAUCAGUGAAGAUGCAAUCAGACAAGUGUUUUGGAAAGAGCACCCUCGAGAAGGGUGGAUGACAGGGCAGAGCAGGAAGGACAGGAAGCUGGCAGAACGGAGGAGGCUGCAGCCGUGGUCCAACCAGGAGCUGAUGGCAGCUGGGGCUAGGGGAAGGGCUUUGAGGGUGGAAGGAUGGGAUGGGUUCCAGAGGUAUUCCUCUCUUAAAUGCAAGUGCCUAGAUUAGGUAGACUUUGCUUAGUAUUGACAACUGCACAUGAAAGUUUUGCAAAGGGAAACAGGCUAAAUGCACCAAGAAAGCUUCUUCAGAGUGAAGAAUCUUAAUGCUUGUAAUUUAAACAUUUGUUCCUGGAGUUUUGAUUUGGUGGAUGUGAUGGUUGGUUUUAUUUGUCAGUUUGGUUGGGCUAUAGCACACAGUUAUUUAAUCAAACAGUAAUCUAGGUGUGGCUGUGAAGGUAUUUUGUAGAUGUGAUUAACAUCUACAAUCAGUUGACUUUAAGUGAAAGAGAUUACUUAAAUAAUUUGGGUGAGCUGCACCUGAUUAGUUGAAAGGCCUCAAGAACAAACACUGCAGUUUCCUGGAAAAGAAGAAACUUUGCCUCAAGACUAUAGCCAUCGACUCCUGCCUGAGUUUCCAGCCUGCUAGUCUGCCCUAUGGAUUUGAAGUUUGCCAACCCCAACAAUUGUGUGAAUUAAUUUCUAAAAAUAAAGCUAUAUACAGCCA